GGAGAGAUCAGCCGCCCAGCCAGGAGUUAAGCUGAGGUCGUCUGAGCCCUGCGACAGCCUGGACAGCAACUCAGGAUGGCAUCAGGCAGGGCACGCUGCACCCGAAAACUCCGGAACUGGGUGGUGGAGCAAGUGGAGAGUGGGCAGUUUCCCGGAGUGUGCUGGGAUGAUACAGCUAAGACCAUGUUCCGGAUUCCCUGGAAACAUGCAGGCAAGCAGGACUUCCGGGAGGACCAGGAUGCUGCCUUCUUCAAGGCCUGGGCAAUAUUUAAGGGAAAGUAUAAGGAGGGGGACACAGGAGGUCCAGCUGUCUGGAAGACUCGCCUGCGCUGUGCACUCAACAAGAGUUCUGAAUUUAAGGAGGUUCCUGAGAGGGGCCGCAUGGAUGUUGCUGAGCCCUACAAGGUGUAUCAGUUGCUGCCACCAGGAAUCGUCUCUGGCCAGCCAGGGACUCAGAAAGUACCAUCAAAGCGACAGCACAGUUCUGUGUCCUCUGAGAGGAAGGAGGAAGAGGAUGCCAUGCAGAACUGCACACUCAGUCCCUCUGUGCUCCAGGACUCCCUCAAUAAUGAGGAGGAGGGGGCCAGUGGGGGAGCAGUCCAUUCAGACAUUGGGAGCAGCAGCAGCAGCAGCAGCCCUGAGCCACAGGAAGUUACAGACACAACUGAGGCCCCCUUUCAAGGGGAUCAGAGGUCCCUGGAGUUUCUGCUUCCUCCAGAGCCAGCACCAGGUAGGGCUGUUCUAUCCCCAGACUACUCACUGCUGCUCACCUUCAUCUACAACGGGCGCGUGGUGGGCGAGGCCCAGGUGCAAAGCCUGGAUUGCCGCCUUGUGGCUGAGCCCUCAGGCUCUGAGAGCAGCAUGGAGCAGGUGCUGUUCCCCAAGCCUGGCCCACUGGAGCCCACGCAGCGCCUGCUGAGCCAGCUUGAGAGGGGCAUCCUAGUGGCCAGCAACCCCCGAGGCCUCUUCGUGCAGCGCCUUUGCCCCAUCCCCAUCUCCUGGAAUGCACCCCAGGCUCCACCUGGGCCAGGCCCGCAUCUGCUGCCCAGCAACGAGUGCGUGGAGCUCUUCAGAACCGCCUACUUCUGCAGAGAUCCUCCAUGUAGCCUAUGCAUGGCACUCCUGCGCUUGUGUGUUGCAUAUCCUGUGUGGCCAUAUGCCCAGCCUGGCAGCUACCUGGCAGCUCUCCUCCAGCCAAGACAAUGGAAGAGGUGGUUCAGACUUGGUCAGGUACUUUCAGGGCCUGGGCCCCCCACCGAAGUUCCAGGUAACACUGAAUUUCUGGGAAGAGAGCCAUGGCUCCAGCCAUACUCCACAGAAUCUUAUCACAGUGAAGAUGGAGCAGGCCUUUGCCCGAUACUUGCUGGAGCAGACUCCAGAGCAGCAGGCAGCCAUUCUGUCCCUGGUGUAGAGCCUGGGGGACCCAUCUUCCACCUCACCUCUUUGUUCUUCCUGUCUCCUUUGAAGUAGACUCAUUCUUCACACGAUUGACCUGUCCUCUUUGUGAUAAUUCUCAGUAGUUGUCCGUGAUAAUCGUGUCCUGAAAAUCCUCGCACACACUGGCUGGUGGAGAACUCAAGGCUAAUUUUUUAUCCUUUUUUUUUUUUAAUUUUGAGAUAUACGCCCUCUUUCAUCUGUAAGGGACUAGGAAAUUCCAAAUGGUGUGAACCCAGGGGGCCUUUCCCUCUUCCCUGACCUCCCAACUCUAAAGCCAAGCACUUUAUAUUUUCCUCUUAGAUAUUCACUAAGGACUUAAAAUAAAAUUUUAUUGAAAGAGGAA